GAGCCUCCAAGUGUCCACACCCUGUGUGUCCUCUGUCCUGCCAGCACCGAGGGCUCAUCCAUCCACAGAGCAGUGCAGUGGGAGGAGACGCCAUGACCCCCAUCCUCACGGUCCUGAUCUGUCUCGGGCUGAGCCUGGACCCCAGGACCCACGUGCAGGCAGGGCCCCUCCCCAAGCCCACCCUCUGGGCUGAGCCAGGCUCUGUGAUCACCCAAGGGAGUCCUGUGACCCUCAGGUGUCAGGGGAGCCUGGAGACGCAGGAGUACCAUCUAUAUAGAGAAAAGAAAACAGCACUCUGGAUUACACGGAUCCCACAGGAGCUUGUGAAGAAGGGCCAGUUCCCCAUCCUAUCCAUCACCUGGGAACAUGCAGGGCGGUAUUGCUGUAUCUAUGGCAGCCACACUGCAGGCCUCUCAGAGAGCAGUGACCCCCUGGAGCUGGUGGUGACAGGAGCCUACAGCAAACCCACCCUCUCAGCUCUGCCCAGCCCUGUGGUGACCUCAGGAGGGAAUGUGACCAUCCAGUGUGACUCACAGGUGGCAUUUGAUGGCUUCAUUCUGUGUAAGGAAGGAGAAGAUGAACACCCACAAUGCCUGAACUCCCAUUCCCAUGCCCGUGGGUCAUCCCGGGCCAUCUUCUCCGUGGGCCCCGUGAGCCCAAGUCGCAGGUGGUCGUACAGGUGCUAUGGUUAUGACUCGCGCGCUCCCUAUGUGUGGUCUCUACCCAGUGAUCUCCUGGGGCUCCUGGUCCCAGGUGUUUCUAAGAAGCCAUCACUCUCAGUGCAGCCGGGUCCUGUCGUGGCCCCUGGGGAGAAGCUGACCUUCCAGUGUGGCUCUGAUGCCGGCUACGACAGAUUUGUUCUGUACAAGGAGUGGGGACGUGACUUCCUCCAGCGCCCUGGCCGGCAGCCCCAGGCUGGGCUCUCCCAGGCCAACUUCACCCUGGGCCCUGUGAGCCGCUCCUACGGGGGCCAGUACACAUGCUCCGGUGCAUACAACCUCUCCUCCGAGUGGUCGGCCCCCAGCGACCCCCUGGACAUCCUGAUCACAGGACAGAUCCGUGCCAGACCCUUCCUCUCCGUGCGGCCGGGCCCCACAGUGGCCUCAGGAGAGAACGUGACCCUGCUGUGUCAGUCACAGGGAGGGAUGCACACUUUCCUUUUGACCAAGGAGGGGGCAGCUGAUUCCCCGCUGCGUCUAAAAUCAAAGCGCCAAUCUCAUAAGUACCAGGCUGAAUUCCCCAUGAGUCCUGUGACCUCGGCCCACGCGGGGACCUACAGGUGCUACGGCUCACUCAGCUCCAACCCCUACCUGCUGACUCACCCCAGUGACCCCCUGGAGCUCGUGGUCUCAGGAGCAGCUGAGACCCUCAGCCCACCACAAAACAAGUCCGACUCCAAGGCUGGUGAGUGAGGAGAUGCUUGCCGUGAUGACGCUGGGCACAGAGGGUCAGGUCCUGUCAAGAGGAGCUGGGUGUCCUGGGUGGACAUUUGAAGAAUUAUAUUCAUUCCAACUUGAAGAAUUAUUCAACACCUUUAACAAUGUAUAUGUGAAGUACUUUAUUCUUUCAUAUUUUAAAAAUAAAAGAUAAUUAUCCAUGAGAAA